AGACCCACGGGGCUGCCCUCCCCUGCGCACUCCCCUCGCUGCCCGGGCCCGGAGCGCAGCGCGGCCGCACAGGUAUUUUUGCUGUGCUGUGCAAGGAACUCUGCUAGCUCAAGAUUCACAAUGUUGAAAGCCCUUUUCCUAACUAUGCUGACUCUGGCGCUGGUCAAGUCACAGGACACCGAAGAAACCAUCACGUACACGCAAUGCACUGACGGAUAUGAGUGGGAUCCUGUGAGACAGCAAUGCAAAGAUAUUGAUGAAUGUGACAUUGUCCCAGACGCUUGUAAAGGUGGAAUGAAGUGUGUCAACCACUAUGGAGGAUACCUCUGCCUUCCGAAAACAGCCCAGAUUAUUGUCAAUAAUGAACAGCCUCAGCAGGAAACACAACCAGCAGAAGGAACCUCAGGGGCAACCACCGGGGUUGUAGCUGCCAGCAGCAUGGCAACCAGUGGAGUGUUGCCCGGGGGUGGUUUUGUGGCCAGUGCUGCUGCAGUCGCAGGCCCUGAAAUGCAGACUGGCCGAAAUAACUUUGUCAUCCGGCGGAACCCAGCUGACCCUCAGCGCAUUCCCUCCAACCCUUCCCACCGUAUCCAGUGUGCAGCAGGCUACGAGCAAAGUGAACACAACGUGUGCCAAGACAUAGACGAGUGCACUGCAGGGACGCACAACUGUAGAGCAGACCAAGUGUGCAUCAAUUUACGGGGAUCCUUUGCAUGUCAGUGCCCUCCUGGAUAUCAGAAGCGAGGGGAGCAGUGCGUAGACAUAGAUGAAUGUACCAUCCCUCCAUAUUGCCACCAAAGAUGCGUGAAUACACCAGGCUCAUUUUAUUGCCAGUGCAGUCCUGGGUUUCAAUUGGCAGCAAACAACUAUACCUGCGUAGAUAUAAAUGAAUGUGAUGCCAGCAAUCAAUGUGCUCAGCAGUGCUACAACAUUCUUGGUUCAUUCAUCUGUCAGUGCAAUCAAGGAUAUGAGCUAAGCAGUGACAGGCUCAACUGUGAAGACAUUGAUGAAUGCAGAACCUCAAGCUACCUGUGUCAAUAUCAAUGUGUCAAUGAACCUGGGAAAUUCUCAUGUAUGUGCCCCCAGGGAUACCAAGUGGUGAGAAGUAGAACAUGUCAAGAUAUAAAUGAGUGUGAGACCACAAAUGAAUGCCGGGAGGAUGAAAUGUGUUGGAAUUAUCAUGGCGGCUUCCGUUGUUAUCCACGAAAUCCUUGUCAAGAUCCCUACAUUCUAACACCAGAGAACCGAUGUGUUUGCCCAGUCUCAAAUGCCAUGUGCCGAGAACUGCCCCAGUCAAUAGUCUACAAAUACAUGAGCAUCCGAUCUGAUAGGUCUGUGCCAUCAGACAUCUUCCAGAUACAGGCCACAACUAUUUAUGCCAACACCAUCAAUACUUUUCGGAUUAAAUCUGGAAAUGAAAAUGGAGAGUUCUACCUACGACAAACAAGUCCUGUAAGUGCAAUGCUUGUGCUCGUGAAGUCAUUAUCAGGACCAAGAGAACAUAUCGUGGACCUGGAGAUGCUGACAGUCAGCAGUAUAGGGACCUUCCGCACAAGCUCUGUGUUAAGAUUGACAAUAAUAGUGGGGCCAUUUUCAUUUUAGUCUUUUCUAAGAGUCAACCACAGGCAUUUAAGUCAGCCAAAGAAUAUUGUUACCUUAAAGCACUAUUUUAUUUAUAGAUAUAUCUAGUGCAUCUACAUCUCUAUACUGUACACUCACCCAUAAUUCAAACAAUUACACCAUGGUAUAAAGUGGGCAUUUAAUAUGUAAAGAUUCAAAGUUUGUCUUUAUUACUAUAUGUAAAUUAGACAUUAAUCCACUAAACUGGUCUUCUUCAAGAGAGCUAAGUAUACACUAUCUGGUGAAACUUGGAUUCUUUCCUAUAAAAGUGGGACCAAGCAAUGAUGAUCUUCUGUGGUGCUUAAGGAAACUUACUAGAGCUCCACUAACAGUCUCAUAAGGAGGCAGCCAUCAUAACCAUUGAAUAGCAUGCAAGGGUAAGAAUGAGUUUUUAACUGCUUUGUAAGAAAAUGGAAAAGGUCAAUAAAGAUAUAUUUCUUUAGAAAAUGGGGAUCUGCCAUAUUUGUGUUGGUUUUUAUUUUCAUAUCCAGCCUAAAGGUGGUUGUUUAUUAUAUAGUAAUAAAUCAUUGCUGUACAAUAUGCUGGUUUCUGUAGGGUAUUUUUAAUUUUGUCAGAAAUUUUAGAUUGUGAAUAUUUUGUAAAAAACAGUAAGCAAAAUUUUCCAGAAUUCCCAAAAUGAACCAGAUAUCCCCUAGAAAAUUAUACUAUUGAGAAAUCUAUGGGGAGGAUAUGAGAAAAUAAAUUCCUUCUAAACCACAUUGGAACUGACCUGAAGAAGCAAACUCGGAAAAUAUAAUAACAUCCCUGAAUUCAGGACUUCCACAAGAUGCAGAACAAAAUGGAUAAAAGGUAUUUCACUGGAGAAGUUUUAAUUUCUAAGUAAAAUUUAAAUCCUAACACUUCACUAAUUUAUAACUAAAAUUUCUCAUCUUCGUACUUGAUGCUCACAGAGGAAGAAAAUGAUGAUGGUUUUUAUUCCUGGCAUCCAGAGUGACAGUGAACUUAAGCAAAUUACCCUCCUACCCAAUUCUAUGGAAUAUUUUAUACGUCUCCUUGUUUAAAAUGUCACUGCUUUACUUUGAUGUAUCAUAUUUUUAAAUAAAAAUAAAUAUUCCUUUAGAAGAUCA